AUGAUGAUGGUUUUAAGGAAUCUGAGCAUGGAGCCCACCUUUGCCCUUUUAGGUUUCACAGAUUACCCAAAGCUUCAGAUUCCUCUCUUCCUUGUGUUUCUGCUCAUGUAUGUUAUCACAGUGGUAGGAAACCUUGGGAUGAUCAUAAUAAUCAAGAUUAACCCCAAAUUUCACACUCCUAUGUACUUUUUCCUUAGUCACCUCUCUUUUGUUGAUUUUUGUUACUCUUCCAUUGUCACUCCCAAGCUGCUUGAGAACUUGGUAAUGGCAGAUAAAAGCAUCUUCUACUUUAGCUGCAUGAUGCAGUACUUCCUGUCCUGCACUGCUGUGGUGACAGAGUCUUUCUUGCUGGCAGUGAUGGCCUAUGACCGCUUUGUGGCCAUCUGCAAUCCUCUGCUUUAUACAGUGGCCAUGUCACAGAGGCUCUGUGCCCUGCUGGUGGCUGGGUCAUAUCUCUGGGGCAUGUUUGGCCCCUUGGUACUCCUUUGUUAUGCUCUCCGGUUAAACUUCUCUGGACCUAAUGUAAUCAACCACUUCUUUUGUGAGUAUACUGCUCUCAUCUCUGUGUCUGGCUCUGAUAUACUCAUCCCCCACCUGCUGCUUUUCAGCUUCGCCACCUUCAAUGAGAUGUGUACACUACUGAUCAUCCUCACUUCCUAUGUUUUCAUUUUUGUGACUGUACUAAAAAUCCGUUCUGUUAGUGGGCGCCACAAAGCCUUCUCCACCUGGGCCUCCCACCUGACUUCUAUCACCAUCUUCCAUGGGACCAUCCUUUUCCUUUACUGUGUACCCAACUCCAAAAACUCUCGGCAAACAGUCAAAGUGGCCUCUGUAUUUUACACAGUUGUCAACCCCAUGCUGAACCCUCUGAUCUACAGCCUAAGGAAUAAAGACGUGAAGGAUGCUUUCUGGAAGUUAAUACAUACACAAGUUCCAUUUCACUGA